GGGGCAAGCAGACAUCAGGGGAUCUCCAGAGACCUGGAUUUCCUCUUUCAGGAACCCGGGACCCCAUCCGGACCAAAGGAACUACCAGAGUUUGGGACCCCUGCCUCCUCCAGUCCUGCUUGCUGGAGAUCUAGGAAAUUAUAUUCUAAGUAUCGGGGCCAGUCUGAGGGAGAAGCCGAGCUCCGCCAUCUCCCAUCCCCACACCCGCUCCUUAGCACCUGCCUAGUUCAGCAUGACAGACUACCAGGAAAAAUAGGGACGCUGAAGGGGGCGGGGGGUCCAGACCUCAGCUCUGGUCGCUGUCCCUAGUGCUGAAGGCGGGGGCGGCGGGGCGGGGCCGAGACUCAGAGUGACUGAGGCGGCAAAGCAGGGGCAGGACCACCACCCAGGUGACUCCCAGAGAAGGAACAGAGGGUGGGGGUGGGGCCAUUUCACAGUCUCCGUCAGGGUGUACCUCUACAUCAAGGUCGCUAGGGGAAGACAGCAGCCCUGUCCUUGGGGGAAAUGAAGGACAGCUCUUGGAUGAGGCAGGGAUGUGUGCAAAGCACCUAACCUGGGGAACUAAAGAAGCAGAGAGGAAGAGGUGUGAAUCUGGAGCCUCGAAAUACAGUUGUAGACCCAGACAUUAUCUUGAAUCCACAUAUAUACACACUCCCUCUAUGUCUCUCUUCCUCCCAUUGUUCCUUUCACUCCUGUCUUUGCUGCCUCGUUCCCACCCAGCCAGUGCGCCUUUUCUAGUCUCCUGUGGAUCUCACUCUCUUCCCUCAGUUCACUCGCAGACGGAUCCCCAGAAGCCUGGUAUCCCUCUGAUUGUGCUUCUCCAUUCUCUAUACUACAUCACCCGCCAGGCUUGUGACCCACCUGUGAGUCAGGCUGUGAAGAUGCUUUCAUGGCUAGGCGAACCCUCUUUCCCUCCCCUCUCUUAGUGUCUCACAAUACAGGAUUCCUCCUCAGCAGCCGAGGAGAGAAAAGAAGAAUGGCCGAGGGUUUUUGUUUAUUGAAAACAUACAGUCUAAGGGGCUUCCCAGAGGCCCGGACUUGAGGAAGUUUCUUUCAGGGCUGAAAAUUGAUUUUGCAGUCCGAGUCAGAAGGGGCUAGCUCCUGAGUUGACACUGGGAUUAGGUGUGUCCUAGAAUUAAAACCACCAUAGGUAACUGAGUCCCUGAGAUUUUCCUGUGCCAUUCUCUGAAUGAGGGCUUCACACAGUUCCCUCUUGACCUCUUCUUUCCACGGUGUCUGCCACAGCAAUGUCACUCACCCCUGCCCAUGCCUCUGCCUGUGCUCAGCCAGAGUCCCAGUGGACACAGGGAGGCCAGAGGAGGAAAGGUUUUACUGGGACCUGAUCAUGCUGCUGCUGAUGGUGGGGAACCUCAUCGUCCUGCCUGUGGGCAUCACCUUCUUCAAGGAGGAGAACUCCCCGCCUUGGAUCGUCUUCAACGUAUUGUCUGAUACUUUCUUCCUACUGGAUCUGGUGCUCAACUUCCGAACGGGCAUCGUGGUGGAGGAGGGUGCUGAGAUCCUGCUGGCACCGCGGGCCAUCCGCACGCGCUACCUGCGCACCUGGUUCCUGGUUGACCUCAUCUCUUCUAUCCCUGUGGAUUACAUCUUCCUAGUGGUGGAGCUGGAGCCACGGUUGGACGCUGAGGUCUACAAAACGGCACGGGCCCUACGCAUCGUUCGCUUCACCAAGAUCCUAAGCCUGCUGAGGCUGCUCCGCCUCUCCCGCCUCAUCCGCUACAUACACCAGUGGGAGGAGAUCUUUCACAUGACCUAUGACCUGGCCAGUGCUGUGGUUCGCAUCUUCAACCUCAUUGGGAUGAUGCUGCUGCUAUGUCACUGGGAUGGCUGUCUGCAGUUCCUGGUGCCCAUGCUGCAGGACUUCCCUCCCGACUGCUGGGUCUCCAUCAACCACAUGGUGAACCACUCGUGGGGCCGCCAGUAUUCCCAUGCCCUGUUCAAGGCCAUGAGCCACAUGCUGUGCAUUGGCUAUGGGCAGCAGGCACCUGUAGGCAUGCCCGACGUCUGGCUCACCAUGCUCAGCAUGAUCGUAGGUGCCACAUGCUACGCCAUGUUCAUCGGCCAUGCCACGGCACUCAUCCAGUCCCUGGACUCUUCCCGGCGUCAGUACCAGGAGAAGUACAAGCAGGUGGAGCAGUACAUGUCCUUCCACAAGCUGCCAGCAGACACGCGGCAGCGCAUCCACGAGUACUAUGAGCACCGCUACCAGGGCAAGAUGUUCGAUGAGGAAAGCAUCCUGGGCGAGCUGAGCGAGCCGCUUCGCGAGGAGAUCAUUAACUUCACCUGUCGGGGCCUGGUGGCCCACAUGCCGCUGUUUGCCCAUGCCGACCCCAGCUUCGUCACUGCAGUUCUCACCAAGCUGCGCUUUGAGGUCUUCCAGCCGGGGGAUCUCGUGGUGCGUGAGGGCUCCGUGGGGAGGAAGAUGUACUUCAUCCAGCAUGGGCUGCUCAGUGUGCUGGCCCGCGGCGCCCGGGACACACGCCUCACCGAUGGAUCCUACUUUGGGGAGAUCUGCCUGCUAACUAGGGGCCGGCGCACAGCCAGUGUUCGGGCUGACACCUACUGCCGCCUUUACUCACUCAGCGUGGACCAUUUCAAUGCUGUGCUUGAGGAGUUCCCCAUGAUGCGCCGGGCCUUUGAGACUGUGGCCAUGGAUCGGCUGCUCCGCAUCGGCAAGAAGAAUUCCAUACUGCAGCGGAAGCGCUCCGAGCCAAGUCCAGGCAGCAGUGGUGGCAUCAUGGAGCAGCACUUGGUGCAACAUGACAGAGACAUGGCUCGGGGUGUUCGGGGUCGGGCCCCGAGCACAGGAGCUCAGCUUAGUGGAAAGCCAGUACUGUGGGAGCCACUGGUACAUGCGCCCCUUCAGGCAGCUGCUGUGACCUCCAAUGUGGCCAUUGCCCUGACUCAUCAGCGGGGCCCUCUGCCCCUCUCCCCUGACUCUCCAGCCACCCUCCUUGCUCGCUCUGCUUGGCGCUCAGCAGGCUCUCCAGCUUCCCCGCUGGUGCCCGUCCGAGCUGGCCCAUGGGCAUCCACCUCCCGCCUGCCCGCCCCACCUGCCCGAACCCUGCACGCCAGCCUAUCCCGGGCAGGGCGCUCCCAGGUCUCCCUGCUGGGUCCCCCUCCAGGAGGAGGUGGACGGCGGCUAGGACCUCGGGGCCGCCCACUCUCAGCCUCCCAACCCUCUCUGCCUCAGCGGGCAACAGGCGAUGGCUCUCCUGGGCGUAAGGGAUCAGGAAGUGAGCGGCUGCCUCCCUCAGGGCUCCUGGCCAAACCUCCAAGGACAGCCCAGCCCCCCAGGCCACCAGUGCCUGAGCCAGCCACACCCCGGGGUCUCCAGCUUUCUGCCAACAUGUAAAACCUUUGAGUACAUCCAGCCUUAGUUCUUGGGGUGCAGUAGUAUGUACCCAAGGGCAGAUGCCUCUUGGGGAAGGCCAUGGGGACCUGAAACAUUGCCCCAUGGAAAUGUCGACCCUGUGCGGACAUUCCGCAUACUGCCAUGAAGACGGUCUCUGUGUCCUCAGCUCAAGAAUCCUGUAGCUUGUCCCAUCAUAAUCCAUUCACCCGUUCAUCAUGUGUACUGAGCAGCUACCAUGUUCAAGGUAAUAUGCCAGGCGCUGUAUGUCUCCACUGCCAAGUAGAAGUGACUCAAAACCCUCUGACAAGGAUAUUCCCUUGGCUAUGGUCCUGCCAGGUGCAGGCCCAGGCCCAUGACCCCACCUUUACUAAGCACAAGUACUUGCCACUGCCAUCACUGCCAAGUAACUAGAUGUCUCUGUUUCCCUGCCAAUGAUCCUGCAGGUUCUGCCCGGUCUGGUUAUCUUCCUGUUCCUGUAGCAUAGCCAGGCACUGCCAGUCACCUGUGCCCCCAUUGCUGUCAGCAGAUGUCUUGGGUCCUGAGUGUGGGUAUCCACUUUUACCCGCUCACUGCCACCUGUGGACACUCUGUGUCUACCCUCUGAGUGGGAACAUACUUCUAAGUUCCCUGCAGUCUCUGUCCUGUGGUAGACCAUCUUUUUGUAAACUGCGAGCUUCCUCUUCCCUGUACCCUCUGCCCCAGUCGUGACCCCCUAAAAGUUAAGGGGUAGUUGGCACCUCCUUAUUAAUAUGCCAGCCUAGAUCCCCCCCGGUGGAGGGGCAAAUGGCUGAAUCCUUGUGUGAUAUUUUUUUCUUCGCUUGUUUAUUUAUUCAUUUAUUUAAUUGUAUUUAUUCAUUUACUAACUUUAUGUGUUACCAAUUAAUUUUGUUUACCCAUUCCUUUAUCCAUCCCUCCCCUCCUUUUCAGGUAAGGAGACAGGAGGAGUAGGAGGAGGCAGGGCCUCUCCAUGCCAGCCUCUGUGGUCCUUGCCCAAACCCAUCAGCGCAAUACUUGAACCUUCUCCCAGGUAGGGGCAGGAGGAGCCACAUGAGAGAGGGAGAAGGACCGCGUUUACCUUUAGAGUUUUGUUUUGUUUUUUCCUUCUGAGUUUGCUGUUGGUGCAGGAAUAAGGGAAAGGCCCAAGGUAUCCAAGCCUGGGGAAGGGCAGGCCAGCCAGCACCUCUGCCUUCUCAGGGACAAGAGUAGUCCUUUACCACCCUCACUCUGCCUGUCCCCUCUCCUACUCUACAGCAUUAAAGACUGUGGGACCAGGACCCUAAGUCUCCUUUCCUUCUGGGUGGGGAGUUCUGGGGUUCUUGGUGUGUGGGAGAAGUUUUAUAAUUGCUUCCAAACAGCUGGGUUUAAAUAUAAAAUAGACACACUCA